AUUCAGUUCUCGAGCUCCAGCCCUCAGCGCAUGCGCAGGACGAGUCGCCUGAGGGAACUGAUCUCAGCUCGGGCCCGCGUUACAUCCUCCUCCUCUUCUUCCUUCGGCCCAGCUUUCCUUAGGGGCUGCAACCCGGACGCCGAGGCCGGUUUCGGAGUGGGGAGUGCCCAUUUUCUCUCCUUCCCACGUUCCUGGCCCCCAGACGCCAUUUGCAGGCGGGUGGCUUGGGUCAGCCUCCCCGCCCCCACCCGACUCCCGUCACGGGAGAGCGCACACCGCGCCCCGAGAACCAAUCAGCAGCCGCGUUAGGUAACCAUGUCUGAGUCUGGACACAGUCAGCCUGGACUCUAUGGGAUAGAGCGGCGGCGACGGUGGAAGGAGCCUGGCUCUGGUGGCCCCCAGAAUCUCUCUGGGCCUGGUGGUCGGGAGAGGGACUACAUUGCACCAUGGGAAAGAGAGAGAAGGGAUGCCAGCGAAGAGACAAGCACUUCCGUCAUGCAGAAAACCCCCAUCAUCCUCUCAAAACCUCCAGCAGAGCGGUCAAAACAGCCACCACCUCCAACAGCCCCUGCUGCCCCGCCUGCUCCAGCCCCUCUGGAGAAGCCCAUCGUUCUCAUGAAGCCACGGGAGGAGGGGAAGGGGCCUGUGGCCGUGACAGGUGCCUCUACCCCUGAGGGCACCGCCCCACCACCCCCUGCAGCCCCUGCGCCACCCAAGGGGGAGAAGGAGGGGCAGAGACCCACACAGCCUGUGUACCAGAUCCAGAACCGGGGCAUGGGCACUGCCGCACCAGCAGCCAUGGACCCUGUCGUGGGUCAGGCCAAACUACUGCCCCCAGAGCGCAUGAAGCACAGCAUCAAGUUGGUGGAUGACCAGAUGAAUUGGUGUGACAGUGCCAUCGAGUACCUGUUGGAUCAGACUGAUGUGUUGGUGGUUGGUGUCCUGGGCCUCCAGGGGACAGGCAAGUCCAUGGUCAUGUCAUUGUUGUCAGCCAACACUCCAGAGGAGGACCAGAGGACUUAUGUUUUCCGGGCCCAGAGCGCUGAAAUGAAGGAACGAGGGGGCAACCAGACCAGUGGCAUCGACUUCUUUAUUACCCAAGAACGGAUUGUUUUCCUGGACACACAGCCCAUCCUGAGCCCUUCUAUCCUAGACCAUCUCAUCAAUAAUGACCGCAAACUGCCUCCAGAGUACAACCUUCCCCACACUUACGUUGAAAUGCAGUCACUCCAGAUUGCUGCCUUCCUUUUCACGGUCUGCCAUGUGGUGAUUGUUGUCCAGGACUGGUUCACAGACCUCAGUCUCUACAGGUUCCUGCAGACAGCAGAGAUGGUGAAGCCCUCCACCCCAUCCCCCAGCCACGAGUCCAGCAGCUCAUCGGGCUCCGAUGAAGGCACCGAGUACUACCCCCACCUAGUCUUCUUGCAGAACAAAGCUCGCCGAGAGGACUUCUGUCCUCGGAAGCUGCGGCAGAUGCACCUGAUGAUUGACCAGCUCAUGGCCCACUCCCACCUGCGUUACAAGGGAACUCUGUCCAUGUUACAAUGCAAUGUCUUCCCGGGGCUUCCACCUGACUUCCUGGACUCUGAGGUCAACUUAUUCCUGGUACCCUUCAUGGACAGUGAAGCAGAGAGUGAAAACCCACCAAGAGCAGGACCUGGUUCCAGCCCACUCUUCUCCCUGCUGCCUGGGUAUCGUGGCCACCCCAGUUUCCAGUCCUUGGUGAGCAAGCUCCGGAGCCAAGUGAUGUCCAUGGCCCGGCCACAGCUGUCACACACGAUCCUCACCGAGAAGAACUGGUUCCACUACGCUGCCCGGAUCUGGGAUGGGGUGAGAAAGUCCUCUGCUCUGGCAGAGUACAGCCGCCUGCUGGCCUGAGGCCAAGGAGAGGAAUGUCAUGCAGGGGACCUCCUGGGUCCGCAGUGUACUGCGAGGGAGCACAGAUGUCCAUCCCCCGCUGGGGUGGAGAGCGGCAGCAGGCCUGAUGGAUGAGGGAUCGUGGCUUCCCGGCCCAGAGACAUGAGGUGUCCAGGGCCAGGCCCCCCACCCUCAGUUGGGGCUGUUCCGGGGGUGACUGUGAGCGAUCCCACCCCAAACCUGAGAUGGGGUAGCCCGUCCUGUGUCCUCCACAGGGACAAGCAGUGGGAGGAGUCUGAAUGGUCACCAGGAAGCCCGGGCUCCAUCUUGACCUCCUUUUUCAGGGACAGGAGCAACAGGCCCCUCUUCCCUGACUCUAAGCCCUUCCCUGUAAGGUGAGGCAGGGUCUGGAGAGCUCUUUAUUGGAACAGAUCUGGUGGUUCAAAUAAACACAGUCAUGCAAGCCUGUUCUUAUGUUCCACUUACUCCUCUACCCACCAUGCAGCUCUGGGAAGCAGGACAAAUUGGACACCCAGCCCUUGCGGGCAGAUGGAGAUCAGUCUCUGCUAAGAAGUCCCUAGAAGGGGUUAUUCUGUUUCCUGGGGUGGCAUCAAGCCUCCCCUGUGUAUGUUUUGGAUGGGAAAAUACACUGGUGCAGCUGAGUACAGCAACUACCCUCGUGUCUUCUGCUCUCACUUAAAGACAGUUACCUGCCUUUGGGUUAAAUGCCCAGUUAAAUACAGUGCCUAGGCUGGGCAUGGUGGCUCACGUCUAUAAUCCUAGCACUUUGGGAGGCCGAGGCAGGCGGAUCACUUGAGAUCAGGAGUUCGAGACCAGCCUGGCCAACAUGGUGAGACCCUGUCUCUACUAAAAAUACAAAAAAAAAUUAGCUGGGCGUGGUGGCGCACGCCUGUAAUCCUAGCUACUUGGGAGGCUGAGGUGGGAGAACUGCUUGAACCCGGGAGGCAGAGGUUGCAGUGAGCCAAGAUCACGCCACUGCACUCUCCAGCUUGGGCAACAGAGCGAGACUCCGUCUCAAAAAAAAAAAAAAAGCCUACUUUUGACUUAAGAAACAGAACUUGUCCUUAAAUGUAGUAAGUACUUACCCUUAAUCCAAAUACCAUGCCUCACCCGUACAGACAGUGCCUUCUGUUGGUUAAAUACAGUGGCUUUCCUCUCGUAAACCUCAUCUACUCUUGCUUAGAAAUGGCAACCCUCACCUUUAAUGUAAAUCCAGAACCUACCCUCAGUUAAAUCCACUCUGCGAUUUGGUACAGUACCAACCCUCAUCUGCUCAGUUAAAUACAGUACAUGAUCUUAGUUUGAGGUUUCCCAAAGUAUGUCUCCAAAUUGGUCUCGCCACCCCAAAUUAAUCCAUCGUUCAGUAAAGCAGUCAGCUCCAGUCCAGCUGGCUGAGUCUGUUCAUCCAUUGCCCUCCCCCACCCCCUGCCGCCCGUGGCACAUAUUUGUCUCCCUGGUUUCCUCCUGCUUUCAAGCAUCCCAUACAGCCCUGGUGUUUCAUACCAUGGGGAUCCAGGGCCUUGUGAGAAACAACUGAAGUGAGGGGGGGCGGGGGGUCAGUGAAGAAAGCACUCAGCAGGGCCAGAGAAGGUCAGGCCAGAAGUGGAUAGAAUGCCAGUCUCUACAGAGGGCUGAGGCCUGGGAGACAGGAGGCCCAGCACAGGCUCUGGCACAGCCACUUCCUGACCGACUGUAGUAGGCAAGGAGCCUCCCCUCUCUGGCCAUUAUUCCAACAUUUAAGAUCAUCCUCGAGGCCCUUCAGAGCUGUGACAUUCACUGCCCUUUUACCGAAAUGCUUCUAAAUCCUUUGCCCCACUGUCGUGAUCUCUACAGAACCCUCCUGACCAUCCUCUCCAGCUAGAUAACCCAGCUCUUCCCUGCCUUGUCAAAAUGUCUGCCCCAAGUCUCAUCCCCACCCCUGCUUCCCCAGGGGGUCUUCCUGCUGGUUGAUUUGGGGGUUUGCCAGAGUAGGAAAGGUGGUGGGGGCAACGGCCAGAGAAAGAUGGGAGACCCAAGGCAAGACGGCACCAGACAGCAUGCAACUCAGUCCAGGAGAGUUGGAGCUUCAGUUUCUUCCAUCCCAGCCCCUUUCAGCACAAGGCUGGGGACAGAGAGAACUGUGCCCUCCCAGCCCUAACCUACCACCUCCUGCUGGCCCAGCUCAGGGCUGAGAUUGUUGAUUGGAUUCACCUGUGAUCUUGUGGUCAGUGUUGCCAAGGAAGGUCUGAAUCAGCACACUCUUGGUGUCCCUGGCUGCCAAAUCCAGGGGCGUGUGAAGCAUCCGGUAGAUGGUGGUGAAGGAGGUGCUGCAGGUGACCAGGAUGCCCGGAUGGGUGAAAUGAGGCACUCUGGAAAUCCGGCCUAGCGUUUCCACCACCACCACCGUGGUGAUCUGGUGACCUUGGUCCAAAGGCCCUGUCCCACCUCCAGGGUUUUGUGCAGGGGCUGGCUCGUUGAGGCAGUUUGACAGAGGAGUCAAACUGGCAGUAGCCUUCUGAACAGUGGGUAAGUAUGUACCGGUCACCCGCCACCCCCUUUACAUCCAGCAGAGGACUCAGGCUGAUGCUGCCAGCAGGCCACUGUGGACACCAGCUAGAUAUACUGCUGCAGGGAGGCCUUCUGCUCUAGGAUGGGCUGCAAGAUGGGCCUGGCCACCAGGAAUGCCUGCUGCUUGUGGCUCUCCAGUCCCUUCAUCAUUCCCAGCAGGUGGAACUCACGCUUUUCAAUUCAGACACAGGAAUACAUUGGUAUCCUUCUCACCCUCCACUGCAGGAAACAUGAGCACCGCUCAAUCAGCUUCUACACUGGAGCAGGCCAUGUUGUGCUGGCAGCUGCCUGGGCUCAAGCGCCUGUCAUGAGCGCAGCACUUGGCCUAAGAAUGUCAGCCCUGCAGCCAGGCUGCCUAUGUUCAGAUCCCAGCCUUGCCAUCUACCACCUGUGUGGCAUUGGACAAGUUGCUAAAGCUUGCUGGGCAUCUGUUUUGUCUGCAAAAUAAGGUGAUGAUUGUACCUACCUCCUAGGGGUGUUGUGGUGAUUAAUUGAGUUCAUAAUGGUGUCUGUUUUAGUCGGUUCUUGCAUUGCUGUAAGGAAAUACCUGAGACUGGGUAAUUUAUAAAGAAAAGGGGUUUAAUUGGCUCAGAGUUCUGCAGGCUGAACCAGAAGCAUGGUGCUGGCAUCUGCUCGGCUUCUGGGGAGGCCUCAGGAAACUUACAAUCAUGGCGGAAGGUGAACUGGGAGCAGGUACUUCACAUGCCCAGAGCAGGAGCAAGAGGGGGCAGGUGGCACACACUUUGAAACCACGAGCUCUUACAACAGAUUCACUAUUGUGAGGACAGUACCAAGGGGCUGGCGCUGAACCAUGAGAAACCACCCCCAUGAUGCCGUCCCUCCCGCCAGGCCCCACCUCCAACAGUGGUGACUACAAACUACAAGUUGACAUGAGAUCUGGUGGGGACACAGAUCCAAACCAUAUCAGUGCCUGACCUAUGCUGAGCCUCAAUAAAUGUUAAAUGCCACCAUCAUCCACAGGUGCCAGGUCUGCAUUGGGCACAUAGCAUUUUGCAAUCCUCUAACUUUGCAAAUAAAUGAGCCAAUACAUACUCUUUCUCCUUAA